AGAGCGCCCCAUGGGCAGGAGCUUUGUGGCUGUGUCAGCUGUGCCACAUCCUCCUGCCCAGCCCGGCCUCCUUCUUCUUACACAGGUGCCACAUCCUCCUGCCCAGCCCGGCCUCCUUCUCCUUACGCAGGUGCCACAUCCUCCUGCCCAGCCCGGCCUCCUUCUCCUUACGCAGGUGCCACAUCCUCCUGCCCAGCCCGGCCUCCUUCUCCUUACGCAGGUGCCACAUCCUCCUGCCCAGCCCGGCCUCCUUCUCCUUACGCAGGUGCCACAUCCUCCUGCCCAGCCCGGCCUCCUUCUCCCUACGCAGGUGCCACAUCCUCCUGCCCAGCCCGGCCUCCUUCUCCUUACGCAGGUGCCACAUCCUCCUGCCCAGCCCGGCCUCCUUCUCCUUACGCAGGUGCCACAUCCUCCUGCCCAGCCCGGCCUCCUUCUCCUUACGCAGGUGCCACAUCCUCCUGCCCAGCCCGGCCUCCUUCUCCUUACGCAGGUGCCACAUCCUCCUGCCCAGCCCGGCCUCCUUCUCCUUACGCAGGUGCCACAUCCUCCUGCCCAGCCCGGCCUCCUUCUCCUUACACAGGUGCCACAUCCUCCUGCCCAGCCCGGCCUCCUUUUCCUUACACAGGUGCCACAUCCUCCUGCUCAGCCCGGCCUCCGCCCUUCUCCUUACGCAGAUGCCACAUCCUCCUGCCCGGCCCGGCCUCCUUCUCCUUACCAGGUGCCACAUCCUCCGCCCAGCCUGGCCUCCGCCCUUCUCCUUACCAGGUGCCACAUCCUCCUGCUCAGCCUGGCCUCCGCCCUUCUCCUUACAAGGUGCCACAUCCUCCUGCUCAGCCUGGCCUCCGCCGUUCUCCUUACCAGGUGCCACAUCCUCCUGCCCAGCCUGGCCUCCGCCCUUCUCCUUACGAGGUGCCACAUCCUCCUGCCCAGCCUGGCCUCCGCCCUUCUCCUUACGAGGUGCCACAUCCUCCUGCCCAGCCUGGCCUCCGCCCUUCUCCUUACCAGGUGCCACAUCCUCCUGCUCAGCCUGGCCUCCGCCCUUCUCCUUACCAGGUGCCACAUCCUCCUGCCCGGCCCGGCCUCCUUCUCCUUACGCAGGUGCCACAUCCUCCUGCCCGGCCUCCUUCUCCUUACCAGGUGCCACAUCCUCCUGCCCAGCCCGGCCUCCUUCUCCUUACCAGGUGCCACAUCCUCCUGCCCAGCCCGGCCUCCUUCUCCUUACGCAGGUGCCACAUCCUCCUGCCCGGCCCGGCCUCCUUCUCCUUACACAGAUGCCACAUCCUCCUGCCCGGCCCGGCCUCCUUCUCCUUACCAGGUGCCACAUCCUUCUGCCCGGCCCGGCCUCCUUCUCCUUACCGGGUGCCACAUCCUCCUGCCCGGCCUCCUUCUCCUUACCAGGUGCCACAUCCUCCUGCCCGGCCCGGCCUCCUUCUCCUUAUGCAGGUGCCACAUCCUCCUGCCCGGCCUCCUUCUCCUUACCAGGUACCACAUCCUCCUGCCCAGCCCGGCCUCCUUCUCCUUACCAGGUGCCACAUCCUCCUGCCCAGCCCGGCCUCCUUCUCCUUACGCAGGUGCCACAUCCUCCUGCCCGGCCUGGCCUCCUUCUCCUUACACAGAUGCCACUUCCUCCUGCCCGGCCCGGCCUCCUUCUCCUUACAAGGUGCCACAUCCUCCUGCCCAGCCCGGCCUCCUUCUCCUUACCAGGUGCCACAUCCUCCUGCCCGGCCCAGCCUCCUUCUUCUUACCAGGUGCCACAUCCUCCUGCCCGGCCCGGCCUCGUUCUCCUUACACAGGUGCCACAUCCUCCUGCCCGGCCCGGCCUCCUUCUCCUUACCAGCAUUUGCUUCUGGGAGGACCCGACCCGAGACACUCACGUAAAAGAGGAUGCCCACGUACAGAUGUGGCAGCAGGCCCUCCGAGCUGGGAUUCAGACCCAGCCUUAAGGAGAAGAAAACCGAGGCCAGGAAGUCAGCAAGAACAUGAAGUCGGUGACCCAGCAUCCAGGUCCCCGGAUUUGCCACCUGUGUCCUUUUGUGGGGCUUCCCUUUGUAAAGCUUGAAAGAAUAAGAGGAUCUUAACAUAAUUUUAAAACUGGAAGAGACCCUGGUGACCAUGUCAUCCGAAGCCCUCAUUCUACCGUGGAGGAGGUGUGGGCCCAGAGAGAAGGGAGGUCCUUGUUGGCGCAGCCGGUGAGCGGCAGGGUGUGUCCCGGAGCCCGGGUUUCCAGCGCCCUCUCUGUCUUGCUGCCGAGCGUCCACGUCUGUUCGGUUGUCUUUGCACACUCCUGGCUCCCAGUUAGACCGCUGCUCCCAGGCGGAACGUCUGCCACAGGGGACACGUACAUGCGGCCACCAUGGGGACUGAAUGAGGGUGGGCCCACAAAGCUCUCCAACGCGGGGUUCUGACAGAAAGCCCAACCCGGGCCGAAAGCCAUCUUUUAAAAUGAAGUUUACUGGGUUUCUUUUUUCAUUAUAAAGUAAUGCACACUGUCCACAGAGAUAUGAAAAUAUUUAAAAGUAGAGAGAAGAAAAACAUCA